ACUUCCGGGCCCUGCGUGGCAGUUGAAAGAGUGGCGGGAGAAGUUGCAGGUGAGCGUCCCCGGUCGCAGGCCUGCGGAUUGGGCAGGGCUUCCCUCCUGAACACCGCUCUGCAGAAUCUUGGUGGCUAAGGUGUCCAGGAGCCUCUGCAGCGGACCGCCAGCCUGAGAGGCGCAGAGCUUGUCGGGCAGGGGCCCGCUUGUCCCACUCCCCUGAUUUGCAGAUGUCAACGGAGGCCCAGCGAAGGGUCAGAGAUGAGGCCCCCUCCCUAGUCAUUCAACUUACUCUACUUAGCCAGCUGUGUGCCAGAUGCUGUACUAAGCGCGGUGGAUGCAUUAUUUUAUUUAAUUCUCACUACCUUAUAAAAUGGGUGCUGUUACCAUCCCUGUUUUACUAAGGAAGAAACUGAGGCCUAGGCAGGUUACAUGUCUCCUUCUGGGUCAUACCUACAGUGUUAGUAAAUGUUCAAGAAAUGAUUAGCUUUGCAUAUGACCCAGCAAUUCUACUCCUAGGUAUAUACACGAAAGGGAUUUGAAAACAUACCCCCACAAAAACUUGUAUGUCAGUGUUCAUAGCAGCAUUAUUCAUAACAGGCAAAAAAAGGAAACAAAUUAAAUGUCCAAGUGAUGAAUGGAUAAACAAAAUGUAGCAUAUCCAUACAGUGGAAUAUUAUUCAGUCAUGAAAAGCAAUUAACUACUGAUACAGGCUACAUCAUAGAUAAACCUUGAAAACAAGCUGAGUGAAAAAAGUCAAUCACAAAAGGCCACAUAGUGUAUGAUUCUAUUUAUAUGAAAUAUCCAGAAUAGGCAAAUGCAUAGAGACAGAUUUAUGGUUGCCAGGAGCUGGGGAGGGAGGGAAAGGACAGUGACGGCUUAAUGGCUGCAGGAAUUCUUUUUGAGGUGAUAAAAUAGUGAUGAUGGUUGCACAACAUUGUGAAUAUACUAAAAUCUACUGAAUGUACACUUUUAAAAGGAUAUUAUGCUGUGCAAAUUAUAUCUCUAUUUUUAUUUUUAUUUUAUUUUUCUUUUGAAGCAGGGUCUCACUCUGUCACCCGGGCUGGAGUGCAGUCGUACAAUCACAGCUCACUGCAGCCUUGACCUCCCAGGCUCAAGCAAUCCUCCCACCUCAGCCUCCUGAGUAUCUGGGACUACAGGUGUGAGCCACCAUACCCAGCUAAUUUUUGUAUUUUUUUGUAGAGACGAGUUCUCACUAUGUUGCCCAGGCUGUUCUCGAACUCCUGGGCUCAAGUGAUCCUUCUGCUUUGGCCUCCCAAAGUGCUGGGAUUAUACGCAUGAGCUACCAUGCCCAGCCUAUAUCUCAAUUUUUAAAAAGAACAGUUUUUGGCCAGGUGCAGUGGUUCACACCUGUAAUCUCAGCACUUUGGGAGGCCAAGGCGGGCGGAUCACUUGAGGUCAGGAGUUCAAGACUAGCCUGGCGAACAUGAUGAAAACGCAUCUCUACUAAAAAUACAAAAAUUAGCCAGGUGUGGUGGUGGGGCGCCUGUAAUCCCAGCUAGGCUGAGGCAGGAGAAUCACUUGAACCUGGGAGUGAGGUUGCAGUGAGCCAAGAUUGUGCCACUGCACUCCAACGUGGGUGCCAGAGUGAGACUCCAUCUCAAAAAAAAAAAAGAAGAACUUUUGACAUCUCCAUUUCAAACGUGAAGAUAAACAAGGGGUUGGAGGUGUUAAAUCUUGUUACCACCUCCCCCCAUUAAAAUUUUGUAAUGGUAACUCUACUUUGUUUAUACUUCAGCUUGACCUGGAAAGAAUUUGAGGAGGAUUCCUGUUAGAUUACCAGGAGUUAGAGUUCCAGAUUGAAUGUGUUGGGGCCAUGUCAUAUUUCUCUGUUUCUGUAUUCUCUAUAUCUUAUAUUUAUGUCAUAAAGCCUGGCUAUGGAACACAGCUAGUGGACUGAAUUGAAUGCUCCAGUCUGUGUCAUAUGUCUCUUUUCCUUUUAGGGAAUUAUUUGAUAGCACAUACUGAUGGCUCUAAAGAAGUCAUCACCCUCACUGGAUUCUGGUGAUAGUGACUCUGAGGAGUUGCCAACAUUUGCCUUUCUGAAGAAGGAACCAUCUUCAACAAAGAGGAGACAGCCUGAAAGGGAAGAGAAGAUUGUAGUGGUUGACAUCUCAGAUUGUGAAGCCUCCUGUCCUCCAGCACCAGAGUUAUUUUCACCACCUGUCCCAGAAAUAGCUGAAACUGUCACACAAACACAGCCAGUCAGGUUGCUAAGCAGUGAAAGUGAAGAUGAAGAAGAAUUUAUUCCUCUGGCUCAAAGGCUUACAUGUAAGUUUCUGACCCACAAGCAACUGAGCCCUGAGGACUCUAGCUCCCCAGUUAAAAGUGUUUUGGAUCAUCAAAAUAAUGAAGGUGCAUCAUGUGACUGGAAAAAGCCCUUUCCAAAGAUCCCUGAAGUUCCCCUCCAUGAUACCCCAGAGAGGAGUGCAGCAGAUAACAAGGACCUGAUCUUAGAUCCAUGCUGUCAGCUUCCAGCCUACCUGUCUACCUGCCCUGGCCAGAGCAGCAGCUUGGCAGUAACCAAAACAAAUUCUGACAUCCUUCCACCCCAGAAGAAAACCAAGCCGAGUCAGAAGGUCCAGGGAAGAGGCUCACACGGAUGCCGGCAGCAGAGACAAGCAAGGCAGAAGGAAAGCACCCUGAGAAGACAGGAAAGAAAGAAUGCAGCACUGGUUACCAGGAUGAAAGCCCAGAGGCCAGAGGAAUGCUUAAAACACAUCAUUGUAGUGCUGGAUCCAGUGCUCUUACAGAUGGAAGGUGGGGGCCAGCUCCUAGGAGCACUGCAGACCAUGGAGUGCCGCUGUGUGAUUGAGGCGCAGGCUGUGCCUUGCAGUGUCACUUGGAGGAGAAGGGCUGGGCCGUCUGAGGACAGAGAGGACUGGGUGGAGGAGCCAACAGUACUGGUGUUGCUCCGGGCAGAGGCAUUUGUGUCCAUGAUCGACAAUGGAAAGCAGGGAAGCCUGGACAGCACUAUGAAAGGGAAGGAAACGCUUCAGGGCUUUGUAACUGACAUCACAGCAAAGACAGCAGGGAAAGCUCUGUCACUGGUGAUUGUGGAUCAGGAGAAAUGCUUCAGUGCUCAGAAUCCUCCAAGAAGAGGGAAACAGGGAGCAAAUAAACAGACCAAGAAGCAGCAGCAGAGACAACCAGAGGCCAGCAUAGGGUCCAUGGUAUCCAGGGUAGACGCUGAAGAGGCAUUGGUGGAUCUGCAGCUACACACAGAAGCCCAGGCUCAAAUUGUGCAGAGCUGGAAAGAGCUGGCCGACUUCACAUGCGCAUUCACAAAGGCUGUGGCUGAGGCGCCCUUCAAGAAGCUCCGAGAUGAAACUACCUUCUCCUUCUGUCUGGAGAGUGACUGGGCUGGAGGGGUGAAGGUGGACCUUGCUGGCAGGGGACUCGCACUAGUCUGGAGGAGACAGAUUCAGCAGCUGAACCGAGUCAGCCUGGAAAUGGCCAGUGCAGUUGUGAAUGCCUAUCCCUCCCCACAGCUCCUGGUACAGGCUUAUCAGCAGUGUUUUUCGGAUAAAGAACGCCAGAAUUUGCUCGCAGACAUACAGGUGCGCCGUGGGGAAGGUGUGACAUCCACUUCUCGCCGCAUUGGACCAGAACUAUCCAGGCGUAUCUACCUUCAGAUGACCACUUUACAGCCACAUCUCUCUUUAGAUAGUGCUGACUGAUUCUAGCCCUCAGGGAUGAGGAUGAAAAGCUGGAAACUUCCACUUCCCCAACCUCAGAGCCUGACUGUAAUGAAGAGACUGGCAGCACCUCCUGGAACACAAGCCUAGGUGAGGCCCAGUCUUUCUUGGGUCUUAUUAUUUGUGAAGGUCUCUCUGCCUGUCGGCUGGGGCAGAGACUGAAAUACUGCCACCUACCUUUGGCAUUUAAUGUUCCUCUCCUGGCAAAAAUUCACUGCCACAGACAAACCACCCCCACUCCUACCCAGCCAGCCCUCAAAACACAAAGGAACAAAGACAGUCCACUCAGACACUUAUUUAAUAACUGUAGAAAUCCAAAAGAAUUAGCAUCAAAUCUUGAAGUCGUGAGUGAAGCUGCGGGUUGGCUUGACUGGGCUCAGCCACUGAGCUGCCUCAACCGGCCAAGGAACGGGAUUAUGAUGACUAUGCGGACUUCUAUAUUGUCUUCAUCUCAUUGUGUGUAUUAUGUAUUUAGUUUCAAUAAAGCAUUUGUACCAAUGGCUCUGGAGCUUGGAGGAAGACUAAA